UCCCAAAGUGCCGGGAUUACAGGCAAGAACCACCACGCCCGGCCUGGACUAUAGAUUUCUUGACAAAGGUGGGAAAUGUGUUUUCCCCAUUGAAUUCCCAGUGCCUAGCACAUAGUAGCCACUGAAACAUGCGUUGAAAAAACAAAGGUUUGGCUGGGCGCAGUGGCUCAUGCCUGUAAUCCCAGCACUUUGGGAAGCUGAGACAGGCAGAUCACGAGGUCAGGAGUUCGAGACCAGCCUGGCCAACAUGGUGAAACCCCGUCUCUACUAAAAAUACAAAAAUUAGCUGGGCAUGGUGGCGCGCACCUGUAGUCCCAGCUACUCAGGAGGCUGAGGCAGGAGAAUCACCUGAACCCGGGAGGCGGAGGUUGCGGUGAGCCGAGAUUGUGCCACUGGACUCCAGCCUGGGUGACAGAGCCAGACUCCGUCUCAAACAAACAAACAAACAAACAAACAAAACAAAAAAAACAAAAAAAAAAACGAAAGGCAAGGCAUUUCAGGAUUUCUUCUAAUAGGAUCUCAGACUAUUCUAGGGAGUUCUGAUUUGUUUGGGAUAUCCCAGUUCUCCUCCUGGGUAUCUUGGAAUGUUGCACUAAGCCCAGAGCAGUUCCAGAGGAGAAUGACAGGCAGAACUAGGUCCUCUAGCUCAUUCUCCCCCGCUGAAAAUCCUGCAUGGCCCUGGACCUCUUUGGAUUCUCAGGUGGUAGGCAAAUGCCUUAGCACUUGCUGUUCCUUCUACCCCUGAGGCUGCUUGGGUUUUUGUUUGUAUAUUUAUUUAUUUAUUAGGGACAAGGUCUUGCUCUGUCAAGGAGUGCAGGCUGGAGUGUAGUGGCGUGAUCACGACUCACUGCAGCCUUGAACUCUGGGGCUCAAUCAAUCCUCCUACCUCAGCUUCCCAAGUGGCUGGAACCAUAGGCGUGUACCACUACACCUGGCUAGUUUAUUUUAUUUUUUCAAUUUUUUGUAGAGACAGAGUCUCCCUGCAUUGCCCAGGAAGAUAUCAAACUCCUGAGCUCAAGCAAUCCUCCCCCUUCAGCCUCCCAAAGCAUUGAGAUUGUAGGUGUGAGCUACUGUGCCCAGCCCUGCCUGCGUUUUUAGAUGUUAGCAAGGAAAGCAAGGGAUAAGUGAGCCAUUUGCUAGCCAACCAGAGUGCCUUGCCAGCCCUGAUCCAGGCGUUUUUCAAAGUCAACUCACUGGAGAAAGAAGGCAAAGGAGAGGGCCCUUGGUGGGCUCUGGCUCUCUCCCCAGCUUUAACCAGAGCAGCUCUGCUGUGAUCUGUGUAUGUAUUGGGAUUCUACUGCUGGGAUGGGGACAGGAGCUCCUUCUCUUGAAACAGACAGCUGAUUGUCUCUCCUCCCUGGCCUUCAGGCUGUGGGCACUGCACAGCAUCAUGGGCUUAAAGGAGGCCAUCCAGAUGUGCUAUUUAUGCAGUCAUUGGGGAAAUGGUCAAAAAGCAAACUGAAGAGGGCUGUCUAGUCACUGGAACCAAGCCACAGCCUGAGGCUCAAAAAAAAUUUGGAAAGUUCCUGACAAGGAGAUGGCAGCAGGUCCAGAGGAAAGUCUGCACAGAUACCAAGCAAGGGGAACACACAGGGUACAGCUCAGAGUCAAAAUGCUGAGUGUCUACUUGUCAGAGAGACGUUGAUAUCACAUACAUGUGUAAUAGGAGCCAUCUAAAGGUAAGACAGAGACAGACAAGGGAGUCUGAGAUCUGAGACAAAGGAGGUCUUGGACUCUGCUCUGCCUGGAUUUCUGGUGGGCUGAAUGAAAUCUGGUGGGUGGGUUGGAGUGGGCUUAGGUGUGGCUAGAGGCUAUGUCUCAGGACUGACUUUGCCCUUGACUUAAAGGACCAGACACUGAGGACCCAGGUCCUCAAAGCUCGUCAAAUUUUAAGGGUGAAAGGGAUAUCAGAAUCACCCAAGCCUUAUCACUACCUGAAUCCUCCUAAUAACACAGUCACAAAGUGGACGCUUGCCCCUGCUCAGCCACUCCCUGUGAGUGGCCAUAGUUGGCAGCAAGGAGCCAGACGCCACAACAAGACUAUGAGCAGACUUAACGCUCCUCUCAAGCAGAUGCCUUGUUGUCCUACAAAGAUUGGCUACUGCUGCCUUACGCCUAAUGACCUUUGGAAUUGGAAAAUUCUUCUCCCCAAGAAAUGUAUGUAUCAAGCUAUAAUGCACCCAGAUUCACCUUGUGCAGCUUUCAUUUCAAUUUUGUCUCUUCCUCUUAUUUUCUUUGCAAAUGGCUUCUAUGUGUAACGACUUUCAUAGCUUAUCCCAGUUCCUACCCAGAAGUGAUGGUAAAUUGCCAAGUUCUCUGAAAAACUCAUGGAAGACUACCAUGUACAAAAUCUGGGGAGACAGGAGUUUAAGACUAGCCCUGGCAACAUAGUGAGACCUCAUAUCUACCAAAAAUAAAAAAUAAAAAAAAUUAGCUGGCCAUGGGUAGUCCCAGCUACUCUGGUGGUUAAGGUGGAAGGAUCACUUGAGGCUGGGAGUUUGAGGCUGCAAUGAGCCAUGGUCAUGCCACUGCAUUACAGCCUGGGCAACAGAGCAAGACCCUAUCUCAAAACAAAAAAAAAAUCUGAGGGGAGACAUCACCUAAGAAGGAGGCUAGAGCCCCAUUGAGGUAGUUAGAUGCUCACCAGUUCUUUCAGCAAAUUCCUCUGCCCCUCCUGCACCCCCUCAUCCUACCUGAAAGGGGAAGGCUCAUUUCCUCUUUUUUCAAAUUGUUAGGUACCUGGAAUUGCUUGCCCUCUCUUGAAUCCCACUCUAGAGGGGUUAAGGAAGGAAGAGGAGGGAAAGAACCUCAUGGUUCUCCUUACCUGGUUGAUCAGGGAACAUUCUGCCAAGCAAUGAAGAUGCUAAAACCCCAGGGGUGAUCCAGCAAUUCCAUUCCUAGGUAUAUACCCAAAGAAUUGGAAGCAGGUGUUCAAAAAAAAUUAUACCCAAUAGUCAUAAUACACUAUUUGCAAUAGCCAAAAGGUAGAACAACCCAAAUGUCCACCAACUAAUGAAUGGAUAAACAAAAUAUAGUGUAUCCAUACAAUAGAAUACUAUUCAGCCAUGAAAAGGAAUGAAGUUCUGACACAUGCUACAAUGUGGAUGAACCUUGGAAACAUGCCAAGUAAAAGAAGCUAGACACACAAAGCGACAUAUUCUAUCAUUCCAUUUACAUGAAAUAUCCAGAAUAGGGAACCCCAUAGAGAAAGCACAUCAGUAGUUGCCAGGGCUUGGGCGGUGGCAGUGGAAGGUGAAUGACUGUUAGUGGAUAUGGAGUUUCCUUUUGGGUUGAUGAAAAUGUUCUGGGACUAGACAGUGGUGAUGGUGGCACAAGUGUGAACCCACCAGAUUCCACUGUACGGAGCACUUUAAAGUGGCUAAAAUGGUUAAUUGUAUGGGAUGUGAAUUUAUCGUAGUCUGUUUGGGCUGCUAUAACAAAAUACCAUAAACUGGGUAGCUUUUAAACAACAGAAAUUUAUUUCUCAUAGUACUGAAGGUGGGAAGUCCAAGAUCAAGGUGGUGUUGUCUGGUGAGGACCCACUUCCUCACUGACAGAGCCUUAUUGCUGUGUCCUCACAUAGUCGAAAGGGUGAAAGUAUCUCUCUCACACUGGGGUCUCUCUGUUGCCCAGGCUGGAGUGCAGUGGCGAAAUCACUGCUCACCACAGCCUCAACCUCCUGGGCUCAAGUGAUCCUCCUGCCUCAAUCUCCUGAGUAGCUGGGACUACAGGAUGUGCUAGGUGUGGGCCGGCCCCCACCCGACCCUGACAAGUGACCAUGGAUCCUGGAGCCGGGUCAGAGACAUCUCUGACUGUCAAUGAGCAGGUCAUCGUGAUGUCAGGUCAUGAGACCAUCCGAGUGCUGGAAGUCGGAGUGGAUGCCCAACUCCCUGCUGAGGAAGAGAGCAAAGGACUGGAGGGUGUGGCCGCCGAGGGCUCCCAGAGCGGAGACCCUGCUGAAGCCAGUCAAGCUGCUGGUGAAGCUGGGCCAGACAACCUGGGCUCCUCUGCAGAGGCAACUGUGAAGUCACCCCCGGGGAUCCCUCCGAGCCCUGCCACUGCCAUUGCCACCUUCAGCCAAGCCCCAAGCCAGCCUCAGGCAUCGCAGACCCUGACGCCACUGGCUGUACAAGCUGCCCCCCAGGUCUUGACUCAGGAAAACUUAGCCACAGUUCUGACAGGAGUUAUGGUUCCAGCAGGGGCAGUUACUCAACCUCUUCUUAUCCCCAUCAGUAUUGCAGGUCAAGUGGCUGGUCAGCAGGGGCUGGCCGUGUGGACAAUUCCUACAGCAACUGUGGCUGCCCUCCCAGGACUGACCGCUGCUUCUCCUACGGGGGGAGUGUUCAAGCCACCUUUAGCCGGUCUCCAAGCUGCUGUGCUGAACACCGCUCUUCCGGCACCGGUACAAGCUGCCGCACCAGUACAGGCCUCCUCGACGGCCCAACCCCGGCCACCAGCCCAGCCCCAGACGCUGUUCCAGACCCAGCCGCUGCUGCAGACCACACCUGCCAUCCUCCCGCAGCCCACUGCUGCCACCGCUGCUGCCCCUACCCCCAAGCCAGUGGACACCCCCCCACAGAUCACCGUCCAGCCUGCAGGCUUCGCAUUUAGCCCAGGAAUCAUCAGUGCUGCUUCCCUCGGGGGACAGACCCAGAUCCUGGGGUCCCUCACUACAGCUCCAGUCAUUACCAGCGCCAUUCCCAGCAUGCCAGGGAUCAGCAGUCAGAUCCUCACCAAUGCUCAGGGACAGGUUAUUGGAACCCUUCCAUGGGUAGUGAACUCAGCUAGUGUGGCGGCCCCAGCACCAGCCCAAAGCCUGCAGGUCCAGGCCGUGACCCCCCAGCUGUUGUUGAACGCCCAGGGCCAGGUGAUUGCGACCCUGGCUAGCAGCCCCCUGCCUCCACCUGUGGCUGUCCGGAAGCCAAGCACACCUGAGUCCCCUGCUAAGAGUGAGGUGCAGCCCAUCCAGCCCACACCAACCGUGCCCCAGCCUGCUGUGGUCAUUGCCAGCCCAGCUCCAGCCGCCAAGCCAUCUGCCUCUGCUCCUAUCCCAAUUACCUGCUCAGAGACCCCCACCGUCAGCCAGUUGGUGUCCAAGCCACAUACUCCAAGUCUGGAUGAGGAUGGGAUCAACUUAGAAGAGAUCCGGGAGUUUGCCAAGAACUUUAAGAUCCGGCGGCUCUCGCUGGGCCUUACACAGACCCAGGUGGGUCAGGCUCUGACUGCAACGGAAGGUCCAGCCUACAGCCAGUCAGCCAUCUGCCGGUUCGAGAAGCUAGACAUCACACCCAAGAGUGCCCAGAAGCUAAAGCCGGUGCUGGAAAAGUGGCUAAACGAAGCUGAACUGCGGAACCAGGAAGGCCAGCAGAACCUGAUGGAGUUUGUGGGAGGCGAGCCCUCCAAGAAACGCAAACGCCGCACCUCCUUCACCCCCCAGGCCAUAGAGGCUCUCAAUGCCUAUUUUGAGAAGAACCCACUGCCCACAGGCCAGGAGAUCACUGAAAUUGCUAAGGAGCUCAACUACGACCGUGAGGUAGUGCGGGUCUGGUUCUGCAAUCGGCGCCAGACGCUCAAGAACACCAGCAAGCUGAACGUCUUUCAGAUCCCUUAGGGCUCAGCCCCUGGCCCUGUGUUCUAGCACUUUGUCCAUUUCCCGUGGCAUCCGGCUGCAGCCACUGCCAUGACAGCACCUGUCAUUUUGCCACGUGCAGCUGUGCUCACCCCAGGUCAUCAGACUCCACCGUGUGCAUGUGCAUCAAUGUCCCUCUUUUCUCCCACACAUCUCACAUCAUGGGGAGGCCAGAGGGGGCCACACGAGAGCUCCAGGCUCUGGGCUGGUCACUCCGAAGAAGAGGAUUUGUGACGUCACUUAGAGAAGCACCUUGCUAGCAUGGUUUCUGAAGGGUGAAUUCUGGUGGGGAACCAGAAACUCCCUGUCUUUGGGGCAGGGCUAAAGCAGCUCCUAAGGACCACUGGCCAUUAGCUCUUGCUUUUGAUGGCAUUCUCUUUCCACCUUGUCUUCUCCUUUGCUCCUCUGUGUUAGUGUGGCAGGUAUGACAACUCAUCCAGUGGAAACACAGCCUCACACUGCCCUUCCGCCCCCCACACUUUGCCUGCAGGUGCACCGAAAGGACCUGGGAGAUAAAAUUCAAAAAAGUGUGAUGUGCUGCUCAGAAGGUCAGACUCCAUGUCUGCCUUGACCUCAAGGUCAGAAGGUUCCCAAACCCCUGGGGCUGGAACAUGGGAUCUCCUCUUCCACCUCUUCCUGGUUCCUUUGCGGGGAAAAUUGCACUAAAACAGAACCUUUUCUUAAUCCAUGUUGGAAGGAAGCAACAGUGAACUCUACCUGUUCUGGAGUUCUCCUGGGUCUGCAGAAGGUUGGGAAUUUAGAAAAUAAGGCUGUUCUUUCAUAUUUUAAUUUAAUCUCUGUCAAUGGCCAUCCCUCCCACAAAAAAACGUGGGUUAAGAGAACUUGCAGACUGGAUAUGCAAGCAAACGGGCAACUCUGGAGAAAAAUAAGGAAAGGAAUGCUGACUUUCUCUUUCUUUCUCUUGUCCCCACACCCAUUCCCAACCCAAUACUGGGGCCUUCUCAAAAGGAGCAAAUUAAACAAUAAACCAGACAGCAAGGCCCUGGGGGAAAGGACAACAUCCUGAAAUAAAUGAUGGAGCCCAGGAAGGUCUCUUGUGGAAGUUGACUUAACUCUAAUUUUCUUUGUAACUUUAAGCCUUGGAUACGGGAGGAGAAAUCUCAUUUUGUCGAGUCUCAGACCAUGUCUGUGUGUAAGCAAUCCCCACAGUGUCCUCUGAGCCAAGGACACCCCCAGAUCAGAUUGAGUUUUGCUUCUAGACGGGGUAGCUAUGGUACCUUGGGGGUUAGCUCUCAUCCAAGCUGUUAAGUGAGUUUCCAGCCUCACUGUGGCUGGAAAGCCCCUAAAAUUCAGUAUGUAACUCCAGGAAGUCAGGAGAGAACUGAGAUUUGCCUAGAUGACCACAGGCUUGCGGUGUAGAUUAUCCCUAAAGGGCCCCAAGUCACGGGGGUCAACCACCCCUGUCUUCAGUACUCUUAUCCUUACAGAGGCUGGUCUCUAACAGCUGCCUCCAGUGGACCUCCCAUGAUCCACCCUGAGGGAAGGACCGUCAGCUGGGGACACAUCACCACCUCUGUCAGUCACUGGUGCAGAGCCACCUCCUAGCCUAGCUUCCUCUGGUGUCCUGUUUCCUUUCCCACUUACUGUUGGUGCCUCCCAGGCCCUGCAGUGCCAGCGUGGCCACCCUCUUGGUAGCCUGGCCAGUAAGAGGAGGACAGUUGUGUGCUGAAUUAGCACACGCACGUGCAGCGCGCACAGACGCGCGCACACACACACACAUACACGCUCUGCUGCAUUUGGACAAACCAUGCCUGCCAGAGUGUAGCAGAGGUGAGGAAGCAGGUGGGCAGCUUGCCUGACCCAGCUUUUCAGGAGAGCGUGUCUCCAACAGAGAGUCUCCACACUCUAGUUCAGGGUUAUCGACCUGCCUCAAUGAGAUGACAGACUCAUUUGGGAGGGGUGUUGCAAACAAGUUUUCAGUGAGAAUAGUUAAGUUCCAGAGCUUGUAAAGGAUUCAGUGACUGACACUUCAGUAAAUUAGGCCAGGCACAUUGGCUUAUGCCUGUAAUUCCAACACUUUGGAAGGCCGAGGUGGGCGGAUCAUUUGAGGUCUGGAGUUCGAGACCAGCCUGACCAACAUGGUGAAACCCCGUCUCUACUAAAAAUACAAAAAUUAGCCAGGUGUGGUAGUGCACAUCUGUAAUCCCAGCUACUUGGGAGGUGGAGGCAGGAGAAUUGCUUGAACCCUGGAGGUUGCAAUGAGCUGAGAUCACACUACUUCACUCCAGCCUGGGUGACAGAGCAAGACUCGGUCUCAAACAAACAAAAACUUAUGGCGAUGCAGGUUUUCAUGCUCAGACGCUUGCAUUCAGGUAUGCUUUCUUUUUUGAGAGAGACAAAUGGGUCACAGCUGGCACCCUGGGAAUAGCACAUAAUCCAGGGUGUGUCUGUGGUGGUGGACGUGCAGGGGAACACCAUCUGUCCUGUGUCAUGAUGGGAAAACAAUCAUGAACCACUGGUCUAAAUUAGGCCUGGCCAUGCUUUCUCAGCCCCUCCCUCAUUUAAAUUUGUCUUCCCAAAGCUGAGCUAAAACUAAACCAUUUCUCCUCUGCUGGAAUGAUGGAUUGGUCAUUCAGAGGAACAAUACCAGGGGUGGGAGGUUUGCAGGCUGAGUUCCCCAGGCAUGGGGGUGCAGGGUGUCCCUGAGGUUUACCCAAAGCACAGCUCGCUGGCCUGUGACCUCUGCCCUUCCUCCCACAGUGUAAGACCCCCCAGGAAGCAGCUGGGGCCUGAACCUCUCACCUAGGAGGUAGGUUUAUUUUAUUUUUUGUUAGCAUCAGGCUCUGAAGGAGUUGGUAUACAUUUUGUUUUGAAAACAUCUUCUGGACUUACACCAGAGCUUAGUGUCGUCUUUACUAUGGAAAGAGAGGAGAAUGGACAGAAAUGGUUUAACUGUGUGGAGUUUUGUUUGUUUUGUUUUAAAUGGAAGAAAGACCAAAACUUUCCUGGUGGAUCAGCUAGGGCCUUUGACCCUGCAUUACCACGGCAUUUUAUCCAGGUGAAGUCCAGGGAAAGAACUCAGCCAAAUGGACUAAGGAACACACGAGUUUGGAAUGCGAGACUCUGACAUUUUUGUGUUCUUGGAAAUCCAAUUACCUUCCCAUGCCCAGAUUUCCUUCCUGCCUCUUGGACCAGGCUCUGGCACUGAGGUUCUCACUGUUCCCAACACAGACAAAGCUUCCUGAGGGCUGGAGGGGCAGCAAGGGGAGAGGAGAAUGGGGAAGAAGCGCUUGAUGUAGUUGUGUGGAAUAAACAGUAUUUUUUCUUUUGUA